CUGCUUGAAGCCUAACUGUCCACCAGAAAGGACUGCUCUUUGGGUGAGUUGAACUUCUUCCAUUAUAGAAAGAAUUGAAGGCUGAGAAACUCAGCCUCUAUCAUGUGGAACAGCUCUGACGCCAACUUCUCCUGCUACCAUGAGUCUGUGCUGGGCUAUCGUUAUGUUGCAGUUAGCUGGGGGGUGGUGGUGGCUGUGACAGGCACCGUGGGCAAUGUGCUCACCCUACUGGCCUUGGCCAUCCAGCCCAAGCUCCGUACCCGAUUCAACCUGCUCAUAGCCAACCUCACACUGGCUGAUCUCCUCUACUGCACGCUCCUUCAGCCCUUCUCUGUGGACACCUACCUCCACCUGCACUGGCGCACCGGUGCCACCUUCUGCAGGGUAUUUGGGCUCCUCCUUUUUGCCUCCAAUUCUGUCUCCAUCCUGACCCUCUGCCUCAUCGCACUGGGACGCUACCUCCUCAUUGCCCACCCUAAGCUUUUUCCCCAAGUUUUCAGUGCCAAGGGGAUAGUGCUGGCACUGGUGAGCACCUGGGUUGUGGGCGUGGCCAGCUUUGCUCCCCUCUGGCCUAUUUAUAUCCUGGUACCUGUAGUCUGCACCUGCAGCUUUGACCGCAUCCGAGGCCGGCCUUACACCACCAUCCUCAUGGGCAUCUACUUUGUGCUUGGGCUCAGCAGUGUUGGCAUCUUCUAUUGCCUCAUCCACCGCCAGGUCAAACGAGCAGCACAGGCACUGGACCAAUACAAGUUGCGACAGGCAAGCAUCCACUCCAACCAUGUGGCCAGGACUGAUGAGGCCAUGCCUGGUCGUUUCCAGGAGCUGGACAGCAGGUUAGCAUCAGGAGGACCCAGUGAGGGGAUUUCAUCUGAGCCAGUCAGUGCUGCCACCACCCAGACCCUGGAAGGGGACUCAUCAGAAGUGGGAGACCAGAUCAACAGCAAGAGAGCUAAGCAGAUGGCAGAGAAAAGCCCUCCAGAAGCAUCUGCCAAAGCCCAGCCAAUUAAAGGAGCCAGAAGAGCUCCGGAUUCUUCAUCGGAAUUUGGGAAGGUCCAUUUUAUGAGCGGCAGAGGUGACUGAGGAGACCCUUCAAACUGCAGUGGAGAAGAGGCUCCCCACACUCCCCCCUCCUUAAAAAUCCUGCAGAGGAAGGGGGAAAGAAAACCAAAGCAUUCUGUCGCCGCGGCAACCAUAAAACCCCCAGCUAAAUCCAUCUUGUGAGCUCACCGCCCCAUUAAGAUGCAGGGCCAGGCGCUGCGCCAGCCCAGCCACAUUCAUUUGUGCGAAUAAAGGUGGAGGAGGGGGAGGGGAGCAGGCUCUGGAGGGACGGGGAAAUGGCGAGAAGAGGUUAUUUACACCACCGUCCUGACCUUCUGGAGCAGCGCUGGCUCCGAUAAAUAACCCGCUCAGCGCCGUUUCAGAGCAGGAGUGGGAGGUGCAGGAAGUGAGCAAGGGCUGGAGAAGAGCCCCCACGCAGGUGCGCGUCUCUGGGUUACUAAUGGCUGAGGCGGGAGCAGGCAGCUGGCUUUGGGGGUGAUGGGGGAAGAACUCAGUUCCCUGGGACUCCCACUGAGAAAAUACCAUCCCCACCCCACCCCUGGCGCCAAUUUCCAGGCGAGGGGACGGAGAGAUGCCAAGGAGGCAAACAGCCCCGUAAAUUAGGGAUGGGGGGGCACUGCUAGGAGUCUCUGAGGUAGGAGGGAAGAAAUAUUAUAAGAUGGGGAAUGACGGGGGGCUGGAGGAACAGGAGUAGCUGCCAAAAAGAGAGGAAGAGAAACAGAAACAUCACACAAAGGCAGUUUGGAAAAAAUGUUUUAUUCCUCUUUGCACAGAGCAGUUUAUGAAGGUGGUUUUCUCCUGACUCCAUGCAUCUUUUACACAAAGAUGCCCCCUUAAAUAUGCCCCGUUAUCUGCCCCACCUCAGUGCUGGAGAACUGGCAGUUAGUAAGUGGGGCAGAAUGCUUAAGUCUCAGGAAGGUUUUUAAAGGCAUUUUUGUGGGGAGGAAGUUCUGGGUCAAGGGGAAAGAUUAGACCCAAGAGUGAGUAUUCCAUUCUCCAUCUUCCUGGGGAAAUCCAAACCCCAAAGGUUUUAUGAAGAAAAGCACCUCUCUCAGCGACCUAGAGACAGGGAGAGCACAGACCUACUGCUUGGGUGUAAGGCUGAGGCAGAGAGAGGGUAGGUUGCAGCGACUGCAGACCCACGGCAGAGAGUAAAUGCAUGUCGGGGAGCUGAGGGGACAGAGACAGCCUAGAGGCCCAAGUCAUAAGUUCCACUCCUUCCCCAGUUCUGAGUAGAAACUUUUCUUCCCAAGACUAGAAUGGAGUUUUAGUUUUAGGAACUGGCUUUGCUCCAGGACACAGAGAAGACAAACCAGGCAACGAUCCCACAGGUAGUAAGGGUGGACAGUUAAGGUAGCUAACUAAGAGAUGGACACUCGCCACUGCAGUUUUGAAGCUAUAUGCCAGAUCAGGGUACAGAAUGCAUUUUAUAUGCCCUGUUCAAUACAAUUUAAAUCGCUGUUUCUUCCAUGUUGUCCCUUCCCUAUGAACUAUUCCCAAAGCCUCUUCCAAGGCAGAGGACAGGGCAGUAAGAAGGAAUGGAAGAAAACACUGAGGUCACUAAGUGGGGUUAGGGCUUAGAUUGGAUAAAUCCCUACCCAUCCCCGCCCCCACUCGUUCUAUAGAAAAGAAUUCUCUUUCUCUCUCCCCUUGCUGGGCUGUUGGGAUGAGGGCCAGGUAGAGGCAAAGGGAGGAAAACACUCAGCACAUUCUUUCUCCUACUUUAAUCUGAAGUGUAGCUACAGCAAAGGGCACAGAAUUUACAAAAAUGUCAGGGCAAGGGAGCAUGUGAGCAUAAUCCAGUCUAGAAAGAAAGAGGGUGCUUCCCCUGCCCUAUUAUCUAAAUAUGCUGGGAGCUUUACUCCCAGAACUGCAAGAAGAAUGAAAAA